AAGCCUCUGUCAGCUCAGCCUCCAAAGGAGCCAGCGUCUCCCCAGUUCCUGAAAUCCUGGGUGUUGCCUGCCAGUCGCCAUGAGAACUUCCUACCUUCUGCUGUUUACUCUCUGCUUACUUUUGUCUGAGAUGGCCUCAGGUGGUAACUUUCUCACAGGCCUUGGCCACAGAUCUGAUCAUUACAAUUGCGUCAGCAGUGGAGGGCAAUGUCUCUAUUCUGCCUGCCCGAUCUUUACCAAAAUUCAAGGCACCUGUUACAGAGGGAAGGCCAAGUGCUGCAAGUGAGCUGGGAGUGACCAGAAGAAAUGACGCAGAAGUGAAAUGAACUUUUUAUAAGCAUUCUUUUAAUAAAGGAAAAUUGCUUUUGAAGUAUA